GUACACUUACGCUGUUAUGUCUUGACGCACGGAGCUUGUCUGCGCCGGCCAGGUGAGUGGGCGGCCUCACCGGGAACCGCUCGCAGCUUUUGGGUUGCUUCAUCGAAAAAGUAGUUCUUGUAUGGUGCUGGGAAUACCGGUGUCCUGGCUGGGGCUCGGUGCUGACAGGAACGGGACGGUGCUCUGGCUAAUUACUUAUGGAAGUCGGCCUUGCGCUUGCGGAGGGGUGUCGGCACCGUCACUUUGGUUCUGGCAGUGGCGGGGGUGUGGUGCUGCUAGUUGUGUUCCUCCGCACCGAAUUUAUGAGUGUGCCCCUGGAGCCCCUGCCGCGGACAAAAUCGGCACCAUAACUUUGGGAUAGGGAGGCUAGAAGGAGGCGGGUGUUACUAGUAGUGUUCCUCCGCCCUGGACGUGUGCGUGUGCGCUUGUGCGGCCGCGGGGUGGGCUCACCUGCCGCCUGUUAAUGCUCCUAGCGCUUGGCCCCUCCCGGGCCGCAGUACUCCUCGUGUGACACGGACAUCAUUAAGCCAGCUGAGAAUCGUGCGGUUACAGCUGCUGCAGUUUCUUUGCAGAGUAAGAGGCUCUUUUUGAAGUUUCCCUGAUGGUGAGGCUUUACCCCUGGAAGUGUCUUAGGAAGAAGACCACUGUUAAAGAUGUCCUAUUCUAGCUUGACAGCCCUGUGGGGAAGACUAAUCCCUUUCUAGAGCACUGGCUUCUCUGGACUUUGCACACCUCCAGGAGAAGAACCCAGAAAAUUGAUCAGUUCUAAAAAACCAUGCCCCACUUGUUGGUGACUUUCAGGGAUGUGGCCAUUGACUUCUCUCAGGAGGAAUGGGAAUGCCUGGACCCUGCUCAGAGGGACUUGUACAGGGAUGUGAUGUUGGAGAACUACAGCAACCUGAUCUCAUUGGACUUGGAAUCCAGUUGUGUGACCAAAAAGUUAUCUCCAGAAAAGGAAAUUUAUGAAAUGGAAUCACUCCAGUGGGAGAAUAUGGGGAAACGUAUCAACCAUCACCUUCAAUACAAUGGUCUUGGAGACAAUAUGGAGUGCAAAGGCAACUUAGAGGGUCAAGAAGCAAGUCAGGAAGGGCUUUACAUGUGUGUCAAAAUUACCUGUGAAGAAAAGGCCACUGAAAGUCAUUCAACCUCUUCUACUUUUCAUCGGAUAAUUCCUACCAAGGAAAAAUUGUACAAAUGUAAGGAAUGCAGACAAGGUUUCAGCUACCUGUCAUGCCUUAUUCAACAUGAGGAAAAUCAUAAUAUAGAAAAAUGCUCUGAAGUUAAGAAACACAGGAAUACCUUUAGCAAAAAGCCAAGCUAUAUUCAACAUCAGAGAAUUCAGACUGGUGAGAAACCUUAUGAGUGUAUGGAAUGUGGAAAGGCCUUUGGUCGUACUUCUGAUCUCAUUCAACAUCAGAAAAUUCAUACUAAUGAAAAACCUUAUCAGUGUAACGCAUGUGGGAAAGCUUUUAUUCGUGGUUCACAGCUCACUGAACAUCAGAGAGUUCAUACAGGAGAGAAACCAUAUGAAUGUAAGAAAUGUGGAAAAGCCUUUAGUUAUUGUUCACAAUAUACUCUUCAUCAGAGAAUUCAUAGUGGUGAAAAACCCUAUGAAUGUAAGGAUUGUGGGAAGGCCUUUAUUCUUGGCUCUCAACUUACUUACCAUCAGAGAAUUCAUAGUGGUGAGAAACCUUAUGAGUGUAAGGAAUGUGGAAAGGCCUUUAUUCUUGGUUCACACCUUACAUACCAUCAGAGAGUUCAUACUGGUGAAAAGCCUUACAUAUGUAAAGAAUGUGGGAAAGCCUUUUUAUGUGCCUCCCAACUGAAUGAACAUCAGAGAAUUCAUACAGGAGAGAAACCCUAUGAAUGUAAAGAAUGCGGGAAGACCUUUUUUCGUGGCUCACAACUUACUUACCACCUGAGAGUUCAUUCAGGUGAGAGACCUUAUAAAUGCAAAGAAUGUGGGAAAGCCUUUAUUUCUAAUUCUAAUCUUAUUCAACAUCAAAGAAUUCAUACCGGAGAGAAGCCCUACAAAUGUAAGGAAUGUGGAAAGGCCUUUAUUUGUGGCAAACAACUUAGUGAACAUCAGAGAAUUCAUACAGGUGAGAAACCCUUUGAAUGUAAGGAAUGUGGAAAGGCCUUUAUUCGUGUUGCAUAUCUUACUCAACAUGAGAAAAUUCAUGGUGAGAAACAUUAUGAAUGUAAGGAAUGUGGGAAGACCUUUGUACGUGCUACACAACUUACAUAUCAUCAAAGAAUUCAUACAGGUGAAAAGCCCUACAAAUGUAAGGAAUGUGACAAGGCCUUUAUUUAUGGCUCACAACUUAGUGAACAUCAGAGAAUUCACAGAGGUGAAAAACCUUAUGAAUGUAAACAGUGUGGGAAGGCUUUUAUUCGUGGCUCACACCUUACUGAACAUCUGAGAACUCAUACUGGAGAGAAACCCUAUGAAUGUAAGGAAUGUGGGAGGGCCUUUAGUCGUGGCUCAGAACUUACUCUGCAUCAAAGGAUCCAUACUGGUGAGAAACCCUAUACAUGUGUCCAGUGUGGUAAAGACUUUAGAUGUCCUUCACAACUUACUCAACAUACAAGGCUUCAUAAUUGAGAAAGCCUUGAAUGUGAUUAAAUUUAAGAAAAUCUUCAUCUAUUUCAUAUCUAUAAUGAAUGUAGAACAUCUUGCUUCUGCUCAGAAUCUGCUCAUUCUUAGAAGGCCUACAUUAACAUGGAUGCAGAAUAAUUUCAGAAACCCCUUAAAUAAUUCCUUAACAUCUCUAUAAACGCUAGAAUAUAAUGCUGAAUUAUAUCCUUUAUUAAGCAUCAUCUCCAUUUCACCAUAUCCUAACUGAAAUCCUAUAUAUUUCUUGUGUGUUCUUUUCUAUUUGUAAAAUACUGUAAUUGUAUUACAAUGACUAAAUUAUAAUUAAAUACAUAUAAUUCCCUUUC